AAAUUAAUACUACUUUCAGAUAAUUAAACUGUCAUACAGCGACUACAAAAUAAUUAUGUUUAAAAUGAUGAGAAAGUUAAAAUAAGGAAAUGAAAACAUAAGAAAAUAAGAGAGUUGGAAAGAAAUCUGGUAAAACUUAUGCAAAUAAAAAAUACAGUCAUUAAAUUUUUAAGAAAUCAGUGAAUGGGUUAAAGGAGGAAUGUGAAUGGAAGCUAAAGGAGAAAUAAGUGAGUGGAAGAAAUAUGUGAAGAAAUUACCCAGAAUGCAGGAAAGAGAGAGGAAAAAAAGAAAAAACAGGAAAUCUUGAGAGACACAGAUGUUGAAAUGGGAAGGUCUAACUUAAUGUCUAAUGGAAGUUGACAAGAGAAAAAGCAAUAUGGAGAUGAAGCAAUAUUUGAAGAGAGAAUGGCUGAAAAUACUGAAGAAUUAAUGAAGGGUAGAAGUCCUUAGAUUUAGAAAGCCUAGGCCAGAUGUGGUGGCUCAUGCCUAUAAUCCCAGCACUUUUGGAGGCCGAGGCGAGAGGAUUGCUUGAGGCCAGGAAUUUGAGACAAGCCUGGGCAACAUAGCGAGACCUCAUCUCUAUAAAAAAUAAAAAUAAAAAAAAAAAUUGAAAGCCUAAUGAGUCCUAAGCAGAAUAAAUAAAAAAUUACUUUUCACCUGGACACAUCACGAUAACAAAGUAUAGCAGAAUUUUUAUGUGUAGCAUUCUACUACUAAGAUGUUGAAAUAGAGUCACCUGAAAUAAGAUUUUAAAUGUCACUUUCCAGUAAUAGCGAUAAAUUUUCACUGGUCUAUCUUUGGUCACUAUUGGUUCAACUUGUGACUUAGAGUAUCACUUUGUGAAGUGUCUGUCUGAUAAGGUUUUCCCAGGGAGCAUUUGUGUCUAACUAUUAACUACUAGUACUAUGGGGAAAAUAUUUCUUUUUGUGACUAGUUUUCUUCUUGAGGGACCUAAGGAAAUACAUUGUCAAGAAAACUAUCACCCAGCUUCCUUCAAAAGAAGUUGUAUGUGUGAGGCAGGGAGUUUAAGGCCAUAGAUUAAAAAUAGUAGCAAAUUUACUUGAAAUUUUAAUAAAUAAAAUAUGUUACCUGUCUUUCUUACUCACUUAUUUAGCCCAGUUUCAGUAUUUUCUUUUUCUGUAUCAUGAAAUCAUUUCUUUUUCUAUUUUCUAUGCUGAUUGUUCUUUCCCUGUUUAUUUAUAGACUUCUAAUGAGCAACUGUAUUUGCACAUCACGUAAAAUGACUUAUUUAUCUAUUGUUUAACAAGUCAAAUGAAACAAAACAAGCAAAACCCACCUUGGCUUUUUUUCUCUAUUUAAUUAGCAUUUCUCUUGAUUUAUUCCCCAUAUUCCUGUACCAUCUGGUCAGCAGACAAAUACAGUGGGGCCUUGCUGAAAAUAAUUACUGCUGUAAUUGUUGUCAUUUCCUCACAUGGGACAACUGUUUUGUUGUGGGCUACAGUCACACAGAAGGCAAUUUGCCUGCUCCUAACAGGUCAGGCACUAAUCCUAGUCCUGCCUUAAGAGUUUUGUGAACUGAAUGUUCCCUGGCCAUUUAAUCUAAUCAGCUUCAUUAAUGAGAUGGUGUGUGUGUGUGUGUGUUGGGAGGGUGGGAAGUAGGGAAGAGGAUUUUCAGACAUCUUUCCCUUUACUAUACAUAUCCUUGAAUAUAUAUGUAUUUAUACUGCUUUUCCAAAGUGUUUUCUCCUGUAAAACCUCUUUAUAAUAUCCUCUGCUUAUUACUAGAUCUCAUUUUUAACUCUAUGUUAUGUAAGUAAAUAUCUAUGUAUAUUUGAGGUAUAAAACUUAAUUCUUUAAGCUUUUUCCAUCUAAUUUUUCUAGUGUCCAGUCUGUGCCUUUGGGCAUCCUUUAUUAAAUUGCUUUAAAUAUCUUCCAAAAGUUUCUCCUCUUAUGAUCAUUCAGUUAUUAAUUUUAAACUAAUAAUUUUUAUUUUAUUCUGUACAUUUAAAAAUUUUCUACUUUUUAUGUCUGCUGCUGAUGUACGUAUUAUUUUAUUAAGGUAUAAAUUUUCAUCAAGGAAAUGUUCACAUUCUCUGUGUACAUUUUCUUAUACAAAAAUGAGUUUAGGCUUUUAAUCUUUUAAUUCAACAAGCUAAGUUUUUCUUUACAGUCAUCCUUACUUGAUAUGUCACGGAUAUUAAAUUAUGUUUGUAUAUUGUUAUUUAGGUGACUAUUAUAUGGUUAAAAAGAUUUUGGAGGAAAACAGUUCAGGUGACUUGAACAUAAAUUGCGUAGAUGUGCUUGGGAGAAAUGCUGUUACCAUAACUAUUGAAAACGAAAACUUGGAUAUACUGCAGCUUCUUUUGGACUACGGUUGUCAGUCUGCAGAUGCACUUUUGGUGGCAAUCGACUCUGAAGUAGUGGGAGCUGUUGAUAUACUACUUAAUCAUCGACCAAAACGAUCAUCAAGACCAACUAUAGUAAAACUAAUGGAACGAAUUCAGAAUCCUGAGUAUUCAACAACUAUGGAUGUUGCACCUGUCAUUUUAGCUGCUCAUCGUAACAACUAUGAAAUUCUUACAAUGCUCUUAAAACAGGAUGUAUCUCUACCCAAGCCCCAUGCAGUUGGCUGUGAAUGCACAUUGUGUUCUGCAAAAAACAAAAAGGAUAGCCUCCGGCAUUCCAGGUUUCGUCUUGAUAUAUAUCGAUGUUUGGCCAGUCCAGCUCUAAUAAUGUUAACAGAGGAGGAUCCAAUUCUGAGAGCAUUUGAACUUAGUGCUGAUUUAAAAGAACUAAGUCUUGUGGAGGUGGAAUUCAGGAAUGAUUAUGAGGAACUAGCCCGGCAAUGUAAAAUGUUUGCUAAGGAUUUACUUGCACAAGCCCGGAAUUCUCGUGAAUUGGAAGUUAUUCUAAACCAUACGUCUAGUGACGAGCCUCUUGACAAACGGGGAUUAUUAGAAGAAAGAAUGAAUUUAAGUCGUCUAAAACUUGCUAUCAAAUAUAACCAGAAAGAGUUUGUCUCCCAGUCUAACUGCCAGCAGUUCCUGAACACUGUUUGGUUUGGACAGAUGUCGGGUUACCGACGCAAGCCCACCUGUAAGAAGAUAAUGACUGUUUUGACAGUAGGCAUCUUUUGGCCAGUUUUGUCACUUUGUUAUUUGAUAGCUCCCAAAUCUCAGUUUGGCAGAAUCAUUCACACACCUUUUAUGAAAUUUAUCAUUCAUGGAGCAUCAUAUUUCACAUUUCUGCUGUUGCUUAAUCUAUACUCUCUUGUCUACAAUGAGGAUAAGAAAAACACAAUGGGGCCAGCCCUUGAAAGAAUAGACUAUCUUCUUAUUCUGUGGAUUAUUGGGAUGAUUUGGUCAGACAUUAAAAGACUCUGGUAUGAAGGGUUGGAAGACUUUUUAGAAGAAUCUCGUAAUCAACUCAGUUUUGUCAUGAAUUCUCUUUAUUUGGCAACCUUUGCCCUCAAAGUGGUUGCUCACAACAAGUUUCAUGAUUUUGCUGAUCGGAAGGAUUGGGAUGCAUUCCAUCCUACACUGGUGGCAGAAGGGCUUUUUGCAUUUGCAAAUGUUCUAAGUUAUCUUCGUCUCUUUUUUAUGUAUACAACCAGCUCUAUCUUGGGUCCAUUACAGAUUUCAAUGGGACAGAUGUUACAAGAUUUUGGAAAAUUUCUUGGGAUGUUUCUUCUUGUUUUGUUUUCUUUCACAAUUGGACUGACACAACUGUAUGAUAAAGGAUAUACUUCAAAGGAGCAGAAGGACUGUGUAGGCAUCUUCUGUGAACAGCAAAGCAAUGAUACCUUCCAUUCGUUCAUUGGCACCUGCUUUGCUUUGUUCUGGUAUAUUUUCUCCUUAGCGCAUGUGGCAAUCUUUGUCACAAGAUUUAGCUAUGGAGAAGAACUGCAGUCCUUUGUGGGAGCUGUCAUUGUUGGUACAUACAAUGUCGUGGUUGUGAUUGUGCUUACCAAACUGCUGGUGGCAAUGCUUCAUAAAAGCUUUCAGUUGAUAGCAAAUCAUGAAGACAAAGAAUGGAAGUUUGCUCGAGCAAAAUUAUGGCUUAGCUACUUUGAUGACAAAUGUACGUUACCUCCACCUUUCAACAUCAUUCCCUCACCAAAGACUAUCUGCUAUAUGAUUAGUAGCCUCAGUAAGUGGAUUUGCUCUCAUACAUCAAAAGGCAAGGUCAAACGGCAAAACAGUUUAAAGGAAUGGAGGAAUUUGAAACAGAAGAGAGAUGAAAACUAUCAAAAAGUGAUGUGCUGCCUAGUGCAUCGUUACUUGACUUCCAUGAGACAGAAGAUGCAAAGUACAGAUCAGGCAACUGUGGAAAAUCUAAACGAACUGCGCCAAGAUCUGUCAAAAUUCCGAAAUGAAAUAAGGGAUUUACUUGGCUUUCGGACUUCUAAAUAUGCUAUGUUUUAUCCAAGAAAUUAACCAUUUUCUAAAUCAUGGAGCGAAUAAUUUUCAAUAACAGAUCCAAAAGACUAUAUUGCAUAACUUGCAAUGAAAUUAAUGAGAUAUAUAUUGAAAUAAAGAAUUAUGUAAAAGCCAUUCUUUAAAAUAUUUAUAGCAUAAAUAUAUGUUAUGUAAAGUGUGUAUAUAGAAUUAGUUUUUUAAACCUUCUGUUAGUGGCUUUUUGCAGAAGCAAAACAGAUUAAGUAGAUAGAUUUUGUUAGCAUGCUGCUUGGUUUUCUUACUUAGUGCUUUAAAAUGUUUUUUUUUAUGUUUAAGAGGGGCAGUUAUAAAUGGACACAUUGCCCAGAAUGUUUUGUAAAAUGAAGACCAGCAAAUGUAGGCUGAUCUCCUUCACAGGAUACACUUGAAAUAUAGAAGUUAUGUUUUAAAUAUCUCUGUUUUAGGAGUUCACAUAUAGUUCAGCAUUUAUUGUUUAGGAGUAUAAUUUUAUUUUAUCUAAAAUAAUAGUCUAUUUUUUCUUUUGUAUUUUGUUAUAAUCUUAAGCAACAAAGAAAAAACCCUAAUAUUUGAAUCUAUUUAUGUCUUUCAAUUUAAAUUCACUUCAGUUUUUGUUAUUGUAAUAUAUUUACUUUUACAUGGUUAUAAUCACUUUAUAUUUUUAAUGUUUUUUUCACUUAAUAUUUUAUAUAUACAUUUCCAUGUAUUGAUGUAGUUAGUCCACAUUUAAAUUUUUAUAGAAUUAUAUAGUUUUUGAAAAAUACAGUCAGUAGAUGUUUUAUUUUUUAGCUAUUCAGUUAUGUUUAUAAGUUUGCAUAGCUACUUCUCGACAUUUGGUUUGUUUUAAUUUUUUUGUAUCAUAAUAGUCCUAUUUUUUUUUCAAGUUGGAGUGAAUGUUUUUAGUUUUAAGAUAGAUAGGAGACACUUUUUUAUCACAUGUAGUCACAACCUGUUUUGUUUUUGUAAAACAUAGGAAGUCUCUUUAAUGCAAUGAUUUGUUUUAUAUUUGGACUAAGGUUCUUGAGCUUAUCUCCCAAGGUACUUUCCAUAAUUUAACACAGCUUCUAUAAAAGUGACUUCAUGCUUACUUGUGGAUCAUUCUUGCUGCUUAAGAUGAAAAGCAUUGGUUUUUUAAAAUUAGAGAAUAAAAUAUGUAUUUAAAUUUUUGGUGUGUUCACAUAAAGGGAUGUAGCUAAAAUGUUUUCAUAGGCUAUUAUAUAUUCUCGCAGCAUUUCCAGUUAAGAGGAUAUUAGGUAUAUAAUUCUCUUCUUAACCGAAUGUCAGAUGGUCUUACGCCACAGGGUGCAGGUAACCCUUGGUCUGUAAGCACCACCGAUCCAGGGAUCAUUGUCUAAAUAGGUUACUAUUGUUUGUUUCAUCUUGCUUUUGCAUUUUUAUUUUUUAAUUUCCAAAUUUUAAGUGUUCCCUCUUUGGGGCAAAUUCUUAUAAAAAUGUUUAUUGUAAAGUUAUAUAUUUUGUCUACGAUGGGAUUAUGCACUUCCCAAUUGGGAUUUUACAUCUGGAUUUUUAGUCAUUCUAAAAAACACCUAAUUAUUAAAACAUUUAUAGAGUGCCUACUGUAUGCAUGAGUUGAGUUGCUUCUGAGGUACAUUUUGAAUGACAGCAUAUUGUAAGAAAAAAAAAGGUGAAUAAAAUUUGACAUUAGAUUAUAAA